ACAACAAAGAUGGCGGCGGCGACUGUGACGGUGACGAAGACGGCGGCGGCGGCGACGGCAUUUAACAAGGCGGUGUGGUUUACUCCAUGCAGUUGUCAGGAGGUAAGUAGCAGGCUGCCGGCUCGGACGGCGGCGACGCGGCAGGACAGGGCGGAUAAGAAGGAGCGGCCGGAGACUGGAGCUGGGUUCGUGGCGGGCCGGCUGAUCCGGACGGAGACUCAGUUCAGUGGAGGGUCGGGCGUGGUCGGUAGGCGGGCAGGUGAUGGCCCGGGACCUCUUUAGCCGGAGGGCAGUGGACUGCGGCGCCUAUGGCCGCGAGAACCCCGAGGGAGCGGGGUCUCCUGCUGUCAUUGCCUUCGAGCAGGAGCUCGGAGGCUCCGGGGCGGGGACUGUUGCUUGGCUCUGACAGGUGGUUCUGCGGGAGGCGUCCCGAGGUUUGCGUCUUCACGGGGUCCCAGGGGCUGGGAGUCAGCCGGGCGCGGGUCUCCUAGGUGUUUCGAAUCCUGGCGAGGAUGUCGCUCCGAAUCUUGGUGAGGCUGCUGCCCCGACGCCGGUCCCAGGCUGAUUGUUGGGAGAAGGACGUUUAAAGCCUUCGUAUUUUAUCUAAUGAUCCUGCCCGGAUCCGUCUCUACUGCAUGGGCACCCUUAUUUUAGGAACAUGUGAGAUUUGAGAAAGACAUUGUAGCAAAUAACUAUUCAGGUUCAUUCGGGGUUUAGAUCUUUGGAUAAACUGUGUGGAGCGCGAGUAGCCAAGCCUAGCAUGCUCGAUGACUGGAUCUGAAGCUAAACAAGUUCUAGCAAACACUAACCACGUGGCCUGCUUAGAGUCCCCUUGAUGUGCUGGUCAGAACCCGAAAGACGUGUGACAAGCGGAAGAAGACAUAAAGGCGUCUUAAAUUGUGUGAUCUGAGGAAAUUCAGUUUUGAAAGAACAGAAUGUAUUUAAAACAACUUUUUUUUAAACACCUCUGUAUGGCUUUUCAAUUUUAGUUGAAAUUCUCUCUCCAUGGCCUUUUGGAGUCCCUUGCUGUAUCUCCGAAGUAAAUUUCAAUUACUCUACAUUUCAUCAAUGUUGGAGUGGCAAGAAAAAGGAGGAACAGAUUUGGGGUGAAAAGUUUUGUUUUCUAGGUCUAACAAACUGUAAAUGUUAAAAAAGCAAAGAUGGGUGAAAAAAAACCAGAGCCUUUGGACUUCGUGAAAGAUUUUCAGGAAUACCUGACUCAGCAGACCCAUCACGUGAACAUGAUUUCUGGAUCAGUUAGUGGGGACAAAGAAGCAGAGGCUCUUCAGGGAGCUGGAACAGAUGGUGAUCAAAAUGGACUUGAUCACCCAUCUGUUGAAGUUUCCUUGGAUGAAAACUCAGGAAUGUUAGUAGACGGGUUUGAAAGGACCUUUGAUGGGAAGCUUAAGUGUCGGUACUGCAACUAUGCCAGCAAAGGAACAGCCCGGCUUAUUGAACACAUCAGAAUCCACACAGGUGAAAAACCUCAUCGAUGUCAUCUUUGUCCAUUUGCAUCUGCUUAUGAGCGUCAUCUGGAAGCCCAUAUGCGUUCUCAUACUGGAGAAAAACCAUACAAAUGUGAAUUAUGUUCCUUCCGCUGCAGUGAUCGAAGUAACUUGUCCCAUCAUCGAAGGCGCAAGCAUAAAAUGGUACCAAUUAAAGGUACUAGGUCUUCCUUAAGCAGCAAGAAAAUGUGGGGGGUUUUACAGAAGAAAACAAGCAAUCUGGGCUAUAGCAGAAGAGCACUAAUCAACUUAAGUCCACCUUCCAUGGUGGUUCAGAAACCAGACUACCUUAACGAUUUUACCCACGAAAUCCCAAAUAUCCAGACUGACUCCUAUGAAAGUAUGGCAAAAACCACACCAACUGGUGGCCUUCCAAGGGACCCCCAAGAACUCAUGGUUGAUAACCCUUUGAAUCAGCUCUCGACUCUAGCAGGGCAGUUGUCCAGUCUGCCACCCGAAAACCAAAACCCUGCAUCCCCUGAUGUAGUUCCCUGCCCUGAUGAAAAGCCUUUCAUGAUUCAGCAGCCCUCUACCCAAGCAGUAGUUUCUGCCGUAUCAGCAAGUAUUCCUCAGAGCUCCUCUCCCACAAGCCCAGAACCUCGGCCAUCCCAUAGUCAAAGGAACUAUAGUCCAGUGGCAGGUCCAAGCAGUGAGCCAAGUGCCCACACGAGCACUCCCAGCAUAGGAAACAGCCAGCCAAGCACCCCAGCCCCAGCCCUGCCGGUCCAGGACCCUCAGCUUCUGCACCACUGCCAGCACUGUGAUAUGUACUUUGCAGACAACAUCCUUUACACUAUUCAUAUGGGAUGUCAUGGGUAUGAAAAUCCUUUUCAGUGUAAUAUAUGUGGAUGCAAAUGUAAAAACAAGUAUGAUUUUGCCUGUCAUUUUGCAAGAGGGCAACAUAACCAACAUUGAUUGAAAAUAGUCAUAUUUUACUUAGUUUUGCUGUUUUUGUGGUUUGGUUUUUUUUGUUUUUUGUUUUGGUCAUCCCUAAUAAAGUGUCUGCUAAUUCAAGGCUUAUACAUUAUAUUUAUAGAAUAUAAAUUUGUCAGUGGAAUAAAAUUUCCCCUUUUUUUCAUAAAAAUCUGGUCAGGGUCAUUUAUAUAUUAGAACAGUUAGACACAUUGGUGUCUCUUUUUUCCUUUCCUUUCGACAUUGGAGAAUUGGAGUGCAGUCAUAAUCUUACAAGAUGUUCAUUUGAAUUUCUCACAUUUAUGGUCCAUAAAAACUUCAAGGCUUAUCCAUACUUUUGAUGUUUCAAUAUGCAUUGAACUGGAUGUUAUUUCUGCCAUAUUUCAAAAUGGUAGAAUAAAUUACAGAAUUUAUUACUACUCAUUUCAGUGUUUAGUACAGAAAUUGCCUUAAAAAUUGCUAUUAAUUGAAAUAUCAUUUAGUUCACAUUCCUUAAGUUGAAUCGGUAGUUUCAUUUCAACUGAUAAUAGUAAAGCUAUUUCAGUUUAGUAAAAAUUUUCUUUUUUCCACAAGAGGAAAUGUAAAACAGUUAAGACUUGAAAUUGAAAAUUCUUUUAAUAUUUAAAAUAACUUGUUUAUUCAAUGUCUAAACACAUGUCAGUUUUCCACUGGAUUUUUAUUUUCACAGGUAAAUACACUAGAGUGCUAGAUGCCUUUUUCCCCUGUCAGUUUGACUUUCAUUUAAAUCCUUCAUUCUGAUAUCAUUACUGUUAGGUGAGGUGGAUAACUAUAAUGAGAAUCUCUUAUUCUUCCUAUUCCUUUGAUGACCAAAGAGAUAAAGUGAAGUCAUCCUUAUUAUUAAAAUGCAGCCUCCAAACAAAUUUCUCAAGAUUCCUUUUCCUUCCUUCUAUCCAUUUUCUGCCCAUAAUUUCCAAGAAAAGGUGGGUAUGGAAACACAUGAGAGAAUGUGAUAGUGAAGUCAUAUUUACAAAACUGAGAACAUGUCCAAAAUGGAUUCUUGUCUCCUCUUCAGAAUUAGCCAUUUAAAAUAUUUUCUGUGACUUCAAAUUGUAAUUCUUAUUUGCAGUUUUACCAGUCUUCAUGUACAGUGACGAAACUGUGUAGAAACUAAAUCAUCGCUUUAGUAAGAAAGGAUAAAAAGGUGUGGAAGUGAAUAUAAAAUGCAUCUAAACAUGACAUUUAAUUUGUUUAUAAAAAUAAGACUUACUAAAUAUAGAGUAAUUCAUUUUGAAUAGGAGGCUAUUGUUUUUAUAUUGUGUAAUAACUCACGUACUCUGAAGAGAGCUUGGUCAAACAAUAAAAUACAUUGUUACUAACUUGGUUUCUUUUCUGUGUACUUUGCAAAAAUUCUAUUUUUAAUUUUGUUCAUAUGUUGAAUGUGCCCCUAAUUGGCAUCUUAAAGAGAAUAGUAAGCAUCUAUUAACCAAAAAAGAACUCUAAUAGUAAAGGAAAGGGAAAUAUUGGUGGUAUGUACCCACAAAACCCCCAAGUGCCAAGUUAAUGGAAUCUCUGCUUUCCCUUUCAGAUGCUAGAAAGCCACUGUAAUGAGUUCUUGCAGUUUAGCAUCCAGUCUAAGCUACUGCAUUGUUUAAAGAGCAGCAUCAAGGACACUUUCUCCAAACUGGAACUCUCUUCUUUGUCAAAUCUUGUACUUUAAAAUUCUACAAUUCUGUUACAUUGUUGUUUAAAUCACAGACUGCUCAGAUCCAUUUUACUGCAGUAGUUUCCAAGUGUGUAACUUGGCUUUAGUAUUUAUCAGUUGCCAGAAAGAAACAGGUUGUCAUUUGGAAGUUUUUGUGGUUAUUUUUUCCCAUUUUUAUUCUUCAGAUAAAAGCAGUACCCCAAAAUAGAAAAUGAAAAUUUUCAUGAAACAAAGAGAACUCCCUUGUUAAAACCAGCUUAUUAACUCUGUAUUCUGUCAAAUGCAUUUUUUUCUAACAACUGACCAUGGAUGUUGUGAAGGUGCAUUUUAAUUUAAACAUGGAAAAGAUUUUUUUCAUAAUUACAUACUAGAAUGUAAAAUUAUAAUUUUGCCAUGACUUAAAGAGCACAGUUGAUAUCCCAAAGGUUUUGAUGCUAAGAAGCUACAGUUAUUCUAAAUGCACUAAAAUGUUUGAGGCAAAUCUACCUUAGAGGCUUUUUUGGUAUGGUAUUUUUUAAAAUAUUUAGAUUUUAUUUAAAUUUCCUGUGAGUUAUUCUGUAUUUGAAAAGAUGUUCGUGUCUUCCCCUCUGUAUUGAAUGUUUCACUCAUUUUAUUUUUAAUCAAAUAUUUUAUAGAAAUGAGUUGUUGGGAAGAGUUUAACAUGCACUAUUUAUAGUACUUUGCCGUUAACAGGCAAUGUUCUGAAACUAAAUUUAUUUUUGUUCAGUGAACAUAAGUUUAGAUUUUUAAAGUUGGUAGAUAAUUUAUCUCCACUAAUAUUUUUUUAAGAAACUGUGAAGAGAUUAACUGGGAAUAAUUUUAUUUCAGAUUUUACUAAUGUAGUAUGUAGCUACAACUUCUUGAACUUCAAGUUAAGGCUAGACAUUUACUUUGAAAAAAUUCCACUGGGUGUUUCCAGGGCUAUUUCAUUUUAGAAAUAAGUGUUUGCCAUUCUUCUGCAAAAACUGGACAAGGGGAAUACUACAAAAAAUACUCAGAGAUAAAAUCCUCAUUUCAAGUUCUACAAAAUAUUUAUCAAAUGAAUGUUAAUUUUUUUUUAAUUCCCUGCUAAAGACGUUUUCAUUAGUCUUAGAGGGUAUAUGCUUUCUAGAACUUGUUUUUGUUAACAUGUGCUUUGAUGUAAAGAACAUAUUUUGUAUGCAAAACAUAACUUGCAUUAUGGUUGUACAAUACACUAUAUUGUUUAGGGAUUCCGGAAAGCAGUUUAAUGCAGAAAUAACUAUAUCUAGUAUGCAGUUCAUAUUGUGAAUGAAGCUUUGCUUUUGUAAUAAAUAAAUAAGACUUUCUAAUGAC